GGGGAACCUAAUCACGGUCUUUAAGAACCUGGACUCAUGCUCCAAUUCUGCUCCAAGUGAGGGCUGGGAGAAGAAAUAUUACAGAGGAACUUGACAAGAGAGGACCUUAAAGAAAGUGAGAUCCUUCAUACUUAGGAAUUCAGUGACACUUGCUGGGAGAAUGCCUUCUAUCAAUGACACCCACUUCUAUCCCCCCUUCUUCCUCCUGCUAGGAAUACCAGGACUGGACACUUUACAUAUCUGGAUUUCUUUCCCAUUCUGUAUUGUGUACCUGAUUGCCAUUGUGGGGAAUAUGACCAUUCUCUUUGUGAUCAAAACUGAACAUAGUCUACACCAGCCCAUGUUCUACUUCCUGGCCAUGUUGUCUAUGAUUGAUCUGGGUCUGUCCACAUCCACUAUCCCCAAAAUGCUAGGAAUCUUCUGGUUCAACCUCCAAGAGAUCAGCUUUGGGGGAUGCCUUCUUCAGAUGUUCUUUAUUCACAUGUUUACAGGCAUGGAGACUGUUCUGUUGGUGGUCAUGGCUUAUGACCGCUUUGUUGCCAUCUGCAACCCUCUCCAGUACACCAUGAUCCUCACCAAUAAAACCAUCAGUAUCCUAGCUUCUGUGGUUGUUGGAAGAAAUUUAGUUCUUGUAACCCCAUUUGUGUUUCUCAUUCUGCGUCUGCCAUUCUGUGGGCAUAACAUCGUACCUCACACAUACUGUGAGCACAGGGGUCUGGCCGGGUUGGCCUGUGCACCCAUUAAGAUCAACAUAAUCUAUGGGCUCAUGGUGAUUUCUUAUAUUAUUGUGGAUGUGAUCUUAAUUGCCUCUUCCUAUGUGCUUAUCCUUAGAGCUGUUUUUCGCCUUCCCUCUCAAGAUGUCCGACUAAAGGCCUUCAAUACCUGUGGUUCUCAUGUCUGUGUUAUGCUGUGCUUUUACACACCAGCAUUUUUUUCUUUUAUGACACAUCGUUUUGGCCAAAACAUUCCCCACUAUAUCCAUAUUCUUUUGGCUAACCUGUAUGUGGUUGUCCCACCUGCCCUUAACCCUGUCAUUUAUGGAGUCAGGACCAAGCAGAUCCGAGAGCAAAUUGUGAAAAUAUUUGUACAGAAAGAAUAAUUCUGUAUUAAAGUUUGGAUAAAUAUAUCUAUAUACAACCCAAAUUAUCAUCAUCUGAGCUCCCUUUUUAAUCUUCUGUAACAGUUGGUCAUGCUUGUCAGAUUUUUUCCUUUUGACUGGAAGUGCUUUAGUGUUGACAGAUAAUGCAAACUUAAAACCUUUGCUGCCUGUUUCCCCUACUUCUCUCCAAGUACCUGGACAAAGGUUAGAGAUUAAUGGAGAAGGUAACUAUGCUGAAGGUUGAGGUGGCUUUGGAGUAGAACUGCUUGUAAACAAGGGUGAUAGGUAGCUCCAUUUUUUUCCAUAUGUCUUCUCUCUAGGUAAGUUUAGAUCCUGAAGGAUACUGAUCAAAUAAAUCUCAUUUUAUAGAUGAACAAAAUAAGCUGUAAUCCAGCAGUAGUGUCCGUUUCAUAGCUUUGUAUUCUUUACAGAAUCCAAAAUUUUGUUGUUCUUCUCCAAAAUCUUUGACUCCCAUGUUUAUUUUAAUGCUCUCUCAGUCUUGCUGUUACUGCCAUUUUUGCUCCUUUCCUUCUUUCAGAUUCCUGCUCUCUCUCUUUUUGUGAUGGUUAAUACUGAGUGUCAACUUUAUUUGACUGAAGGAUACAAAGUAUUGAUCCUGGUUUUGUCUGUGAGGGUGUUGCCAAAAGAGAUUAACAUUUGAGUCAGUGGGCUGGGAAAGGCAGACCCACCUUCAAUCUGGGUGGGCACCAUCUAAUCAGCUGCCAACGCAGCUAGAAUAUAAAGCAGGCAGAAAAAUGUGAAAAGACUAGAUGGGCCUAGCCUCCCAGGCUACAUCCUUCUCCUGUGCUGGAUGCUUCCUCCUCGAACGUCGGACUCCAAGUUCCUCAGUUUUGGGACUCAGAGUGGCUCUCCUUGAUCUUCAGCUUGCAGAUGGCCUAUUGUGGGACCUUGUGAUCAUGUGAGUUAAUACUUAAUUCCCCCUUUGUGUGUGUGUGUAUGUGUACACACACACACACACACACACACAUAUAUAUAUAUAUCCUAUUAGUUCAGUCCCUCUAGAGAACACUGACUAAUACACUUUUCUUUUACAUUCGUUCUCUGAUAAAGUAAGUCUUUGUGAAUUUAGGGAUAUGAGAGACUACAGUGUGGGUAUUACGGAGACAUGUUUUCUCACUUGAAGCAAAGUCAUUUUAGAUGUGACUACUUGUAUGUGUCGCCUGUCUAAUUCUAAUUCUCAAUUCUAUCUGACAAUUUCCCUUCAGACAAAAUAUAUAAAACUUAUGAGACUUUAUAAAACUUAGAAAAACAAUUAGGCUCAAGCUAUGGUAAGCACAGGGCCAGACUUGAUAUCGACUUCAAAAUAAUAUCAUUAUAAUUUAUUAAUCCUGUAGAUCUCCAAUAUUUAGUCCUAUUUUCAAACUUCAGAUAUGGCUGGAGAAUGUGGUUUGCUUUAAAAUAGAUAAAAGAGACAUUGAACUGAAAUUUGUGACUUAUCAGGGUACUCAUGCUUCAAAAUCAGAAGAAGUCUCCCUCAUGUUCUAUAAUUUAGAACCACUGUGUAGUUUGUAUGACAAUAUACAAAAUACUCAAAAGUACGCAGAUAACGAUUUUAGGAAAUGGGGGCGGAUAUAGCCAAGUAGACAAGAAAAGCAACAUCACCUAUUCAGUAUCUGUGAAUCUGGACAGUUCUUGGUCUUAACACUGGCUAAGCACAAUUCCUGAAUUCUAUAGUAUUUUGUAGAUUUUCUUUAGGUCUGUAUGCAUGGGUUCUAAUUUGAUUUUUGCAGCUUCUGCUUCAUGUACUUAACAUUUUAUGGGAACAUAGGGUUUUAAAUGUGGAAAUACAUUGAAACUUGAUCUAUUCCCUUUGUCUUACAAAUAAAA